GGUUUCCCUGGCAACUGGAGCAAUCAGAGCACCGCAGCCAGGGAGAUGCUGGCGAGACGACAGCGAGAUCCUCUCCAGGCCCUGCGGCGCCGCAAUCAGGAGCUGAAGCAACAGGUUGAUAGUUUGCUUUCUGAGAGCCAACUGAAAGAAGCUCUAGAACCCAAUAAAAGACAACAUAUUUAUCAAAGAUGUAUCCAGUUAAAGCAGGCAAUAGAUGAAAAUAAAAAUGCUCUUCAAAAAUUAAGCAAAGCUGAUGAAUCUGCACCUGUUGCAAACUAUAAUCAGAGAAAAGAAGAGGAGCAUACUCUUUUGGACAAGCUUACCCAACAACUGCAGGGCCUUGCUGUGACAAUAAGCAGAGAAAAUAUAACUGAAGUUGGGGCACCUACUGAAGAAGAGGAAGAAAGUGAAAGUGAAGAUAGUGAAGACAGUGGUGGGGAGGAAGAAGAUGCAGAGGAGGAAGAGGAAGAGAAAGAGGAAAAUGAAUCUCACAAAUGGUCAACCGGUGAAGAAUACAUCGCUGUUGGAGAUUUUACUGCUCAGCAAGUUGGAGAUCUUACAUUUAAGAAAGGGGAAAUUCUCCUUGUAAUUGAAAAAAAACCUGAUGGUUGGUGGAUAGCUAAGGAUGCCAAAGGAAAUGAAGGUCUUGUUCCCAGAACCUACCUAGAGCCUUAUAGUGAAGAAGAAGAAGGCCAAGAGUCAAGUGAAGAGGGCAGUGAAGAAGAUGUAGAGGCGGUGGAUGAAACAGCAGAUGGAGCAGAAGUUAAGCAAAGAACUGAUCCCCACUGGAGUGCUGUUCAGAAAGCGAUUUCAGAGGCGGGCAUCUUCUGUCUUGUUAAUCAUGUCUCGUUUUGCUACCUAAUAGUUCUGAUGCGAAAUAGGAUGGAGACUGUGGAAGACACCAAUGGAUCUGAAACAGGGUUCAGGGCAUGGAAUGUACAGAGCAGAGGACGUAUAUUUCUGGUUUCUAAGCCUGUGCUCCAACAGAUAAACACUGUUGAUGUGUUAACUACGAUGGGAGCUAUUCCUGCAGGGUUCAGGCCUUCCACGCUCUCACAGCUUCUGGAGGAAGGGAAUCAAUUUCGAGCAAAUUACUUCUUACAACCAGAGCUCAUGCCUUCACAACUGGCCUUCAGAGAUCUGAUGUGGGAUGCUACAGAAGGCACUAUUAGGUCGAGACCAAGUCGUAUUUCAUUGAUUCUGACAUUAUGGAGCUGUAAAAUGAUUCCUCUUCCAGGAAUGAGCAUACAGGUUCUCAGCAGACAUGUACGCCUCUGUCUAUUUGAUGGUAAUAAGGUUCUGAGCAACAUUCAUACAGUCAGAGCCACAUGGCAACCUAAAAAGCCCAAAACAUGGACCUUUUCUCCCCAGGUUACUCGCAUCUUACCAUGUUUGCUUGAUGGUGAUUGCUUUAUCAGGUCUAAUUCUGCAUCUCCAGAUCUUGGAAUAUUAUUUGAACUUGGAAUUUCUUAUAUUCGCAAUUCAACUGGUGAAAGAGGAGAGUUAAGCUGUGGCUGGGUGUUUCUUAAACUUUUUGAUGCCAGUGGAGUUCCUAUUCCAGCAAAAACUUAUGAGCUUUUCUUGAAUGGUGGUACUCCUUAUGAAAAAGGUAUUGAAGUGGACCCUUCAAUAUCCAGAAGAGCACACGGCAGUGUUUUCUACCAGAUUAUGACAAUGAGAAGGCAGCCUCAACUUCUAGUGAAACUGAGAUCCUUGAACAGAAGAUCAAGAAAUGUACUAAGUCUACUGCCAGAAACAUUAAUUGGAAAUAUGUGUUCUAUUCACUUGUUGAUAUUUUAUCGACAAAUUCUUGGAGAUGUGCUCCUGAAAGACAGGAUGAGCUUGCAAAGUACUGAUUUAAUUAGCCAUCCCAUGCUGGCCACCUUCCCCAUGCUCUUGGAGCAGCCUGAUGUGAUGGAUGCUCUCAGGAGUUCGUGGGCUGGAAAAGAAAGCACAUUAAAAAGAUCAGAGAAGCUCUCAAAGCCUGUAUCACCAAGAGAAGGGAAAAAAAAAUGGCCUGAGCUGUACCAUAUAUUGAAAACAAUGCAUUGCUCCUGCUUACCUUGCUAUAAAAUCAUGGGUCUGACAUCCUCAUCACCAAAGGACCCCUCGACCUCCAUCCCAGGCAUUGCUGGAAAUAAGCCAACAACUCUGGAUCCUAUGCAGAACACCUGCUACAAUUAUCUUAGAUAACAUGACAGUUACCUCUGAUAUGCUGUCAAGAGACAAAGAGUUCCUGAAGUCCACGUUUCUCCUGGUUUACCAUGACUGCGUGCUCCCACUUCUCCACUCCACACGCCUACCCCCAUUCAGGUGGGCAGAAGAAGAGACUGAGACUGCACGGUGGAAAGUUAUCACUGACUUCCUUAAGCAAAACCAAGAAAACCAGGGCGCCCUCCAAGCUCUGCUGUCACCAGACGGAGUUCAUGAACCUUUUGACCUUUCAGAGCAGACCUAUGACUUCUUGGGUGAAAUGAGAAAGAAUGCAGUGUGACAGUGGCAGCCUCUAGCCCUCAGCUUCCCACGGAAUCAGAUGGAUCCUCCACGAUUACGUGAAUAAAAUGAUGGAACCAAAAAUCACUGUCACUUUACAACUUAGGUUUUACUCUUUUCUUUCUACAGACCAUAUUUUUAAAGAAAUGUUUAUACAAUAAUUUAAAUAUUUUUUAAAACCAUAAAAUAAAUUUUUAUAAGGAAUACUGUUAUAUCUAAAUUUAAACAGUAUUUAUUUUUUCAAAAACAGCUACUUAAGUUAAUGGUAUAGAUUUCUAUAAAAGCAAGAUUUUGUCAAAAACUAAAUUUAUGAUUAUUCAAGAAAGUGAAAAAAACAACCUACAGAAUGGGAAAACAUAUUUGCAAAUCAUCUAACUGAUAAAGGUCUAGUAUCCAAAAUAUUUAAAUUUAUGAGUGUUAAUAAAAUUUAUCUUGUUCAAUGAA